AGAGCUGGGGACUUCGCUGGAGAGAUGGCACCGGCCUGAGGUCAAGGAGAAAUUGAACUAAACUCUCCUUUGAAGACUGUUUCCAGAGGCCCGUUCCCGAAGCCGGAGUCCCGACCCGAAACCGUCCCCGGCCGGCUCGCUCGCUCAGCAGGGCGCGGCUCCAGCGCCACCCGGCUCGCCCCGAAGAGGUGGGACUUUCCCCACCGGAAGUGAUCCCGUCCAGUCUCGGGGAACUGGGGCACCUCAGCCAGUGUGUCAGGGAAACCCUUCCGGCAGCGCUGGGGCAGCGGAGAGACAGAGGAGCCAGCGGGUGGCCAUGGCCUUGGCGUGACAGAGCCUCCCCGGCGGCCGGGCGGGUGCGGACGGCGGGGCCGGACGACCCCCGCGGGAGCCGGGGCCCAGAAACCCGCCCGGGCAGCGGUAACUGGAACGGAGCCCUCAGGCCUGAGCCGGCUGGGCUGCGCGAGCAGGAAGCGGGGUCCCUGGGCCCCUUUGUGUGAAGGGCGGGGGAGGAGUGCCGGGCAGCCCCGGGCUGCGGGCUCCUCCGACGUCCGCCUCGCCGCAGGGUCCCCUCGCCGCAGCCCCCACCCUUUCCCUCCCGGGGGCACGCGCCUCCUCGCCACCCUCGCCGGGCUUUUCCCAGGCUCGCCCUCCUCCCCACGCCCCCUGCUCGGGCUGCAGUUCCUAUAGGAAGGGCAUUACCAUCCCUUCCCCACCCUCCCCGACUCUACGCUCUUUCCCCUCCCCCUCCUGUAACUUCCUCUUCUUCCCCGGUUGGGCCCUCUGCUCCUCUGCACUCUCCUCCCCAGUUCGCAGAUUUCCGCCCACCUUCCGCCUCGUCUAGCCGCGCCACAGCUAGCGGGGUGAUCUUUCCCCCCCUCUGGUAGGAGUUGGUGAAGGUGAGACUCAUGAGGGAAUACAAGGUAGUGGUGUUAGGGAGUGGAGGGGUUGGCAAAUCUGCCCUUACUGUGCAGUUUGUCACUGGGACUUUCAUUGAGAAAUAUGACCCCACCAUUGAAGAUUUCUACCGCAAAGAGAUCGAAGUGGACUCUUCCCCCUCCGUGCUGGAAAUUCUGGACACCGCAGGAACUGAGCAGUUUGCCUCCAUGAGAGAUCUCUACAUCAAAAACGGCCAAGGUUUCAUCCUGGUUUAUAGCCUGGUUAAUCAACAGUCUUUUCAGGAUAUCAAGCCAAUGAGAGAUCAAAUUGUCAGAGUGAAGAGAUAUGAAAAAGUCCCACUAAUCCUAGUAGGAAAUAAAGUGGAUCUGGAACCAGAAAGAGAGGUUAUGUCUUCAGAAGGCAGAGCUCUGGCUCAAGAAUGGGGCUGUCCUUUCAUGGAGACAUCGGCAAAAAGUAAAUCAAUGGUGGAUGAACUUUUUGCUGAGAUCGUCAGGCAAAUGAACUAUUCAUCCCUGCCGGAGAAGCAAGAUCAGUGUUGUACAACUUGUGUCGUCCAGUAAAGAAGAUAACCUCAAUCAUGGCCAUACCGAGCAGAUAAAACUCAGAGGAAAUUUGCACAGAUGCUGCUUUGGAGAACUUUACAACCUGGGUUGCAGAACUGAGCCUUGGUAAACCUGUCUCUAUUACAGCAUGUUGCCAUACAUCUAUUUAAGUGCAUAAGGUCUUUGGCCUUCAAGAUCCAUCGACCUUAAACAGGAAUGCUUAGCACGUUUACCAUACGUUUAAAAUCCAUUCUUUAUCAAUCAGUCCUUUUAUAGCUUUCUAAGUUCUUAUUGAUGGCUAAUAUACAAGGGUUAAUUUUUAAUAUUUUAAUUGAUUUCUUUAAUCAGUUUCUCGACUUGUAUUUAUUAAAUACUCAAACUCAGUAUUACCUACUCAAUGCCUUUUAAAAGAAAGUUAUAAUGGAGAAAAAAUUGAGCCUUAAACAAAUGGUUACUUCUGUAUAUUACCUCGUACCAGUGCUUCAUCCUAUUUGUAAAAUCUUUCUCCUUUAAAAUUAUUGGUUAAUACUUUGAGACUUUGUUUACGUGUGGCAGUGUUGUAAAAAGAAACUAAAGAUCACAUUUUACCUGUAUGGAUGGAAUAUCCCUUUUCUUCAAGUGCAGUUUGUGAUGUGUUUUGUUUUUUUUUUUUUUUUUUUGUAAUUAACAUGUUCUGAAGGUUACAAUUGAUAUUUGAAAUUGACUGUAGAGCAUUUAGUUGAAGAGUUAAGCAUUCAGUUCCAUUAGGUUUUCACAUGUGUUAAUCUCAUUUACAGCAUUGAAUUGCGGCAGUAACAUUUUCCUUUCUGUGAAGUUCUAAAUUUAGUUAUGACCUAUUUAGCAAUGCCUUUGAAAAGGGAUAUUGUAUCCAUGGUAAAUUAAUUGUAUACCUAAACAGAGAUAGCUCAUCUUUGCCUAUCAGGCUUGUAAUUGACAUCUAGUAGACUUCUGCACAUGUAAAAUUGAAUUCAAAUAAAAUCAUACACACUUUCUAGUUCUUAAUAUUUGUCUUUCUGAAUAAUAGUUUAAAGCAAUAUUUGUUAAAGUUUUCUUGCACUAUCACAAUUGCUUUUUAGUUAUUUCUCAAGAAGCAUGUUCGUAUUAGAGACAAAAUCUGUGUAACAGGAGGGAGAAUAGCGCCAAGUCUCUGGGCUAUUUUUUAUUUUUGCAAAUGUGCUUUCUAAUAGCCAUUGCCUUCCAUGUUGUUUACCUAAUCAGCAUAUUUUUGUCUGAAUACUUGAACAUUUUAACAGUAACGCAGGUGUAGAAUCAGAAAGGAAACUUAUGCAGAGUAAUAUUUUGGUUCAGUUUUAACAUCGUGACAAUGAGGGCUUUUUCUAGCAAUGAUUUUUAAAUUGUGUAAGUUUGACAGUAUUUUAUUGUUGGGUUUUUAUUUGAUUUUAGUUGUGUGCUUUUCAUUUGCAGAAGUUAGUAACUGCAGCUCACCUACUGCACCAAAGUUCUCGAUUUUAGGAGCCCAGCUUUAGUCAUUUGAACAUGCUUCUAAAUAAAAUAAAACAAAACCAAAACUAUACUUUUGAUCUAUAAUAAGAGCUCAAUAACUUUGUCAAGGAAAGCUCUAAUAUAUGCAGUGAUGGUUUAUGAAAGGGUGUGGCAAUUUUAAAUUUAUAUUGUGUGUGAUGUUCAAAUAAAGUGGUAUCUACAUUCAUGUGAUUUAUGGGUCAGCAUGACCAUUAAUUACUGAGUAGAAAUUGACUAAACUUUGAUUUCCUUUUUUUAAAUCGUGUUGCAUUUGAUUCCUGAGCAAAUUCCCUCAAAGUGAACUCUUGUUCUUAAAUUUUGAAUUUUAUGGUGAGAUUGUAAAGAUAGAGGCAAUUGAAACAUUGUUCCUUAUUUAUGAACUGCUUGAAGUGAAUACUUAAUUUAAGUUUGCACUUUAAUACCAAACUUAAAACCAAACACUCAUUUAAAAGUAGGUUAAGUGAUCAUGGAUCAUUGUUAUUAGCUUUGUGGCUUUGUGAAAUUCUAAAGGAAUCAAAUAAUUCAUCAUGAUUUAAAUUUUCUAGAGAUUUUGAUUUUUUUAUAAUGUUUCUUUCCUGUAGAUUGUGUUCUUGUUUCUCUCUCUCUCUCUCUCUCUCUCUCUCUCUCUCUCUCUCUCUCUCUCUCUCUCUCAAAAUUACAGUGUUCAUUGUCAUUGACCUCAGCAGCAAAUUUGACUUGAAUUCACUUAGGAUCGCAGGAAUCAGGGGAAAGUGAUUUUAAAGGUGGUUUCUCCAGCACAUUUUAAGAAAAGGGACCAAAAGUUAUUUUAGCUUCCUCAAUAGAUUGCAUGUUGCUUAUUAGGAUAAUAAAUUAAUAUUAAAUGCAAUAUAUGUCUUGUCUUUAUUAUGGCAUCUAUUUAGGAGUUGUUCAAAUCACUGCAGUAGGGCUCUGCAAAUAAAAUAAUGUAACCUAUUAUCAUGGAUCUAAUGUACUGUAACUUUAUCAGUGAAAGGUAAAAUCUCAAAUAACAAGUACAAACAUUGAACAAUUACCUAUAAAGAUUUGUAAAAGUAAAAUUUUUCCAAUAGAUUUCAUUCUUGUCAUUUUGUAAGACGACCCUGCAGUCCACCUGUUUGUAACUUUUUUAAUAAAAUAGACAUCUGUAUUACUGA